CCUGCCCGGACGGCCGUCCGGCUCCGACCCGCGGGAGGGGGCGGAGAGAGCACCCCAGUCCCCGCCGUCCGCGCCCCCAAAGCGCGUGACCCCGUCUCCUCUGGCCCGGACCCCCCCUCCUUUCCCUUGACGCCACCACCACGUGCGAAGCCUGAGCCCGGGCAGGGGAGGGGGGAGCUGGUGGGAUCCAGCCCCCUCCCUCCCGCUCCCUACCUCCCGGGCGGGAGACCCAGCCCCCCCGGCCUGGGAGCCUGGCUGGGGGCUGAGCGGAGCGGAGGAGCGGGUGCCCCCCCAGGGACCGGGCCUCUGCGGGUUCUGGGAGGCGCUGCCCGGGCUGGCUGGCGGGGGCGCACGGUGGGCCGCGGCGGGAGGUUGCUGUCCACCCGGGCCCGGACACCCAGUCGGCGCCCACUAAAUGUUGGCGGAAUGCAGCCAGGAGUUGGCGGCGAGGCGGGGGGAGGCAGCAACUCCUCUCCCCCCAGUCAGGCGGCGGAAGUCACAGAGGUGCUGGUGCCCCUGCCACCCGCGGCACCCACCUGGCUCACCCAUGGGUGGCGGGCUCGGUGGGCCCCCCCACCUCCCUGCCAGCUGCCUCCGGAGAGGGCGUGGGGAUUCCGUGUCAGUGCCCCCCGCCCCAACCUCAGAACUGGACCAGGGCGUAACCCUGAGCGUGCCGCUCCCACACUGGGGGUGCCUCCCCACCACCGGCCGAUCACUUCCUAUUGGCAAACUGGUCUGGGAGAGGUCCCGGGGAGGCCAGGCUGGGGCAGGGGCCCAGGCCAGGCCAGGCCUAAGCCCAGCCCUGCUGCUGCCAGGGCCUGAGGGCUUCAGGCCGGGGGCGUUUGUCCGCGAGGGCCACCCGCCAUGGGGCCCCGAGAGCACCUAUCGGCGGGGCCGGGGCCUCUGUUUACCACCAGCCAUCGCUGUGGAGACAGAGCUUGGGGGAGAAGGGGGGGCAGGAGCCGGCCGCUGGAAAAGCGAAGUCUAAGGAAGGAAAGAAGAGCCAACCGGGACACUGAAAUUUUAAUUCGUGGGUCUCGGCGCGGAAGAUGGCCGGCGGCGUGGACGGCCCCAUCGGGAUCCCGUUCCCCGACCACAGCAGCGACAUCCUGAGUGGGCUGAACGAGCAGCGGACGCAGGGCCUGCUGUGCGACGUGGUGAUCCUGGUGGAGGGCCGCGAGUUCCCCACGCACCGCUCGGUGCUGGCCGCCUGCAGCCAGUACUUCAAGAAGCUGUUCACGUCGGGCGCCGUGGUGGACCAGCAGAACGUGUACGAGAUCGACUUCGUCAGCGCCGAGGCGCUCACCGCGCUCAUGGACUUCGCCUACACGGCCACGCUCACCGUCAGCACAGCCAACGUGGGUGACAUCCUCAGCGCCGCCCGCCUGCUGGAGAUCCCCGCCGUGAGCCACGUGUGCGCCGACCUCCUGGACCGGCAGAUCCUGGCGGCCGACGCGGGCGCCGACGCCGGGCAGCUGGACCUUGUAGAUCAAAUUGAUCAGCGCAACCUCCUCCGCGCCAAGGAGUACCUCGAGUUCUUCCAGAGCAACCCCAUGAACAGCCUGCCCCCCGCGGCCGCCGCCGCCGCUGCCAGCUUCCCGUGGUCCGCCUUUGGGGCGUCCGAUGAUGACCUGGAUGCCACCAAGGAGGCCGUGGCCGCCGCUGUGGCCGCCGUGGCCGCGGGCGACUGCAACGGCUUAGACUUCUAUGGGCCGGGCCCCCCGGCCGAGCGGCCCCCGACGGGGGACGGGGACGAGGGCGACAGCAACCCGGGUCUGUGGCCAGAGCGGGAUGAGGACGCCCCCACCGGGGGUCUCUUUCCGCCGCCGGUGGCCCCGCCGGCCGCCACGCAGAACGGCCACUACGGCCGCGGCGGAGAGGAGGAGGCCGCCUCGCUGUCGGAGGCGGCCCCCGAGCCGGGCGACUCUCCGGGCUUCCUGUCGGGAGCGGCCGAGGGCGAGGACGGGGACGGGCCCGACGUGGACGGGCUGGCGGCCAGCACGCUGCUGCAGCAGAUGAUGUCAUCGGUGGGCCGGGCGGGGGCCGCGGCGGGGGACAGCGACGAGGAGUCGCGGGCCGACGACAAGGGCGUCAUGGACUACUACCUGAAGUACUUCAGCGGCGCCCACGACGGCGACGUCUACCCGGCCUGGUCGCAGAAGGUGGAGAAGAAGAUCCGAGCCAAGGCCUUCCAGAAGUGCCCCAUCUGCGAGAAGGUCAUCCAGGGCGCCGGCAAGCUGCCGCGACACAUCCGCACCCACACGGGCGAGAAGCCCUACGAGUGCAACAUCUGCAAGGUCCGCUUCACCAGGCAGGACAAGCUGAAGGUGCACAUGCGGAAGCACACGGGCGAGAAGCCGUACCUGUGCCAGCAGUGCGGCGCCGCCUUUGCCCACAACUACGACCUGAAGAACCACAUGCGCGUGCACACGGGCCUGCGCCCCUACCAGUGCGACAGCUGCUGCAAGACCUUCGUCCGCUCCGACCACCUGCACAGACACCUCAAGAAAGACGGCUGCAACGGCGUCCCCUCGCGCCGCGGCCGCAAGCCCCGCGUCCGGGGCGGGGCGCCCGACCCCAGCCCGGGGGCCACCGCGACCCCCGGCGCCCCCGCCCAGCCCAGCUCCCCCGACGCCCGGCGCAACGGCCAGGAGAAGCACUUUAAGGACGAGGACGAGGACGAGGACGUGGCCAGCCCCGACGGCUUGGGCCGGUUGAAUGUAGCGGGCGCCGGUGGAGGAGGUGACAGCGGAGGUGGCCCCGGGGCCGCCACCGACGGUAACUUCACAGCCGGACUCGCCUAAAAACCAAAAAGAGAAAACAGAAACCCGAGAAAGAGAGAGACAGAGAGAGAGAAAAAAAAUCACCCACCACCCCCCCAAAAACACAAAAAAAGAAAAUCUAUCUAUAUACAGAUAUCUAUAUCUAUAUAUAUAUAUACAGAUAUAUAUAUAUGACGCGUCACAGAAUCUAGGGUAGCGCUUUCUCAGAUUUCCCUCCUUUCUGACGUUUUUCUCCCUCCGCAGGGGCCCCGGCCCUCCCUGGCUCCCCUUCCCCCCACCACCCCAUCGCUGGGUUUCGGGGCUUGGUUUGGGGUUUUUUGUAGGACACAAGGAAUCCGAGACCCCGCACAGCCCCCUGGGCACCCGGCAUGGGGCCUGGGGCCCGAUCCGAGGCCCUGGGCUGGGGGGAGGGUAGACGUGGGGGCGCUGGGGGGGGACUGGGGUGGGCUUUUAAUUUCCUCCCCUCGCUGGUUUCUAUGAGUCUUUCAGACAAGACCUUAAAUGAUUUCUGUCUGCUCUGAGCGGACGUUAAAAUGGGCCCCCGUCCCCCGACCCGCACCCUCCUUCCUCAGGGCACUUACUAAGGGAGGGGUCUCCCUCUCCAUCUCCCCAGUGGCCUCCCCGCCUCCAACCCUGCCUGCGGCCUCCCCCCGUCGCCCACCCCACGUCUCCUGGCCACUGAGACACAAACCUAUUUAUUUCUAGGCCUGGAGAAAGGAGAUCGGACUGGGGUUCCCGGUGGGGCGCCAGGAUGGCUCCUGGGGGUGCUCCUGCCGCCUUCCUUCACGGCACUUACAACCGGCGGGACCCCCAGGGACCACCCCUCAGGGCGCCCCCCCACCCCCGCCCGGUCCACCUAGACCCCCACGUUUGGAGAUUCAAAACUUCUGUCUUCGUCCUCUCCCCCGAGCCCCCUCUCCCAAAUUUUUAAAGCACUUUUUAGAUUUUUUUUUCUCUUUCCUCCUUAAAAACAAAAUUUAUAUAUAGAUAUAUAUAUAUAUAUAAAUAAUAUACUUUUCCUCAGAGGAGCAGGCAACAGUGUGGGAUAAACAGAGUCACGAUCAGAGGAACCCCAGGGUCUGGUGAUGGCAGGGAUGGGGGGAGAGAGAGAAAAUCCACAAAUUCCAAUGUCACAAAAGCAAUAAAACAAACUAGAAAAAAAAAAGGUUUUACAAAAUGAAAGGAAGGAAAAAAAAAAAGGCAACCAACCACAUUAGAAGUCUUGGCACUUUGUAACGGAACGGGUACUACACUUUAUCUUAAUUCUUAAUUUAAAAACAUGUUUACAAGUUACAACCAACUUCUAUGAAAAGUUGAAAAGACAAAAAAAAAAAAAAAAAGCGAGCGAGAGAGAGAGCGAGAGAGAGAGCGAGAGCAGAAGAAAUUCCUAAAAGUCGAUUUAUUUUUGUACAAAAUAAUAAAAAAAAAAACCCACCACAAACGUAGAAUCCACUUCUGUUCCCCAAAAAGCGAGAAGGGGGGUUCAGGAGGAAGCCAUCGCAGGGGACCUGGGAGACGCCCCGAGGUGUUUGUGCUUCACCCCCAGACGUCAGCCUCGAAGGCAGGACUGUGGGGUGUUCGUGCUGUGUUCCCCCCGCUCCCCCUUUCUGUCCCCUUUUUUGGUUCUGACGUGAAGAGGUCUUAGCGCCCGCUUCUGUCCACGGGGUCUCUCCUUCCUCCUCCCUAGCUCAGGGAUGGGCCUUCCAGCCGGAGCACCCCGAUCCCCAUCCGGCACCCCCCAAUCCCCCAACACGCCUGUCCCUCCCGCAUGGCCACCAAGGAGCUGGACCUUGGAUGCGCCUACCCUGCUGAGGUGGGUGACAGGGGCCCCCCACCUCCAGGGCCUUAGAACCACCGCCCCUCUCCCCACCCCAGGCACCCCUCUUUUUACUCAAAGGCACUGACUGUAAUCCAGGGGGACUGGGACCUGCCUCCCCCCAACCUCUGGCUCCCACAAGGCCCGGUGUUGACCGAGCCACAGGCCACGGACAGGGGCCGGGGUUGGGGAGACUAUGUCGCCAGAUGCCAGGACGCCCUCACCCCGUUUGCAUAUGCAAUGCUAGCAUGGGACCCCGAAAAUAGACGCUCUGCUGCACUGAGACUUCUUGUCAAUGCCCAACCGGCGGGGGGGUGUCUCCCUGCCCCCGACCCCCCCAUACCCCCUUCUCUGUGACACACACAUCUUCUCGUCUCUUUUUCUUUCAUUGUUAAAGGGAAGCUUUUUAAGAAGGCAAUUUUCAUAUUGUUUCUACAGGAUGGUUUUGGUUCCCUUCCCUUCCCACCCCCCCUUAAGCCUGUCAGCCCCCUCCAAAUGUCUCAGGAUCCCCCCUCUCCCCUGGGGCUGGGUGACAGCACCCCGGCUGCGUUCACACCCCAGUGUCACAGGGCGAGCUGUUCUGGAGAGAAAACCAUCUGUCGUGGCUGAGCGGGGAGCUUGAACACCCAGGCCAGGGACACCCCUCCCCAGCUCCCAGAGAGGCCCCCUGAGGGGUGAGCCCUCUUUCCACCUUCCCCUAUCCAUGCACCCCCUCGCAAUAAAACCAACUCUAAAAUCACAGCUGUCGUCCUAGCCAGUGGGGGCGACCGGACUUGGGGGGUGGAGCCCUCUGGGACUUCCGUAGGAACAAGGGCUGCGGCCCACCGCGACACUUACACAGACCUCGGGGAUUGCACUAAACCCUCGUUCCUAGCUCCGCACUCAGCUUCGCCUGUCCUGCCCGCCCACUUUGCCUUAACUACCCGCCCGUCCUGGGGGCCACAGCCUCUGCAUGGGCCCAGAGCCGGGACCCCCCCAGCCCAGCCCCGCCCUCCCCAGACUCCGCGCAAUCACAUACUGUAUAUAGACGUGAAUCGAUUUUAUUUUUAUUCUUUAAAUUAAGGUCGUGAUAAAGUGUUGCCAAAGAUACCUGCUGAAUUCUCGCGUUUCAGGAAACAAACAAACAAAAAAAAAUGAUAUUUGAGGAGGGUCGUGUUGACUCCAUAUGAAAGGACACAGCUCAAAGCUUUUUUGUUUGGUUGUUUGGGGUUUUUUGUGUUUUCUUUUUUUGGGGUGUUUUUUUUUUAACUGCCUGGUACAAAAAAAAAAAGAGAAAAAAAAAAAAGAAAAACAAUGCGAAAUUGUUAUUUCCAUUCUCAUGGUGAAGUUGCGUGGACGCGUGUGUGCGUGUGUGCAAGAGAGCGGGAGUGAGGUCCAGGCUGGGGUUGGGGGGCUUCAGGCGGGGGCGCCCGGGGGCCGGGGAGGUGGCCGGGCCGGAGCCCCCGUCUGCAGUGCCCCCCAGCCUGCCGGGCCCAGGAGAGAGAGAGAAGCAUCUUUGCUACUAGCUGUUGCUGCUACCUGCCUCUGCCCCCCGACGCCCCCCGCCUUUUGAGAUUAAGGAAAAAAAAAAAAAGUCAAAAAAGUUUUUAAAAAUGAAAAAAAAAAAUUAUAAACCAGUGAAUGUAAAAUGCCGGAGCAGGCCCGGCCUGGCAUGGGUGUGGACCUGCAGCCAGGCAGGCUCGAGCGGGCGAUACCAAAGUCUGCCCCCCCACCAUUGUGGCCAUGCAGUCCUGUCACUGUCUUUUUGCUUCCUUCCGAGGGGGGUCCCCCAGCCUCUUCCAGGGUCUUCCCCUGGAAGUGGGCGGCUGCAGGGAAGGUGGGGGACAGGGGUCUUUGCACGAUUCAGACCCCGGGGCCGUGGCAGGAGCGGUCACCUCACAGGUGGUGACACUGAGGCAGGGGCCUCGGGGUGCCCCCUCCCGCCCGGCAACCAGAAUGGUUGGAGGCAAGACAGAGAGAAUGAAAGGAAAAACAGAAGAAAAAAAAAUAUUAAAAACCAACAAAAAAAGCAAAAAUCCUAUUUUUUGAGAAAGAAAGAUAUUUAUAUUUGCAGUUUUAUUUUAAAAAGUUAUUUAAGUUGAAGCAGCCUUCCUGGAGGUGGGGGGGGGGGGGUGGUGGGUGGCUGGCGCAGGACGGGUCAGGGGCCUGGAGGCUGGGGGUGCCCCAGGAGCUACAACCUCAGAGUUAAGACUAGCUCGCAUUAAAUACAUAGAUUUACGGGGGGGGGGGGGGGGGGCCGGGCCCAGGGGGUGGAGGGGGCCAGGGAGACCCCCAUCCCUCGCCGGGGCUGCCUGGAGGCUGUGGACCAGGAUCCGAUGCCCAGGUCCCGCCCCCCACCCCACCCCAGGCCCAGAAUCGAGGUGCCUUGGACUUUGGAGGGGCCAGGCCUGGUGAAUGGGGGGCGGGGCGGCGCCCUCAGGGUACAGAGCACAGACAGAUAGACAUUCCAGAGACUGUAUUGAGAGUCUUUAUAAAGUGUGGGAGAUUUAAAAAAAAAAAAAACUGAUAAAAAUGCACUUUUUGGGAGUGGGGAGGGAGAAGCUUUAAAAGUAAUAAAAAACAAACAAAAACACAAAAGAUGAAAAAACAAAAAAAUUCAUUUUUCUUGUACAUAAAAAAAAAAAAAGAACCACUAAACGCAGCCUGUUACGACC